AUUCCCAGAGCCGGGGCUGGGGCUCUAGGCUGCCGCGGCGGCUCUAGGCUGGGCUGCUGGGCGCGAGGCCAGGGCGGGCCGGGAGAGGCUGCGCCGGCGGCGGAUCGCGCAGAGGGCGGUGGCCUGGGCUGGCCGAACCAUGGCGGCCCCGGAGCCGGCGCCGAGGCGGGCCCGGGAACGGGAGCGGGAGCGGGAGGACGAGAGCGAGGACGAGAGCGACAUCCUGGAGGAAAGCCCGUGUGGUCGCUGGCAAAAGCGACGGGAGCAGGUAAACCAAGGGAACAUGCCAGGGCUUCAGAGCACCUUCCUAGCCAUGGACACGGAGGAGGGGGUAGAGGUGGUGUGGAACGAGCUCCACUUCGGAGACAGGAAGGCCUUCGCGGCGCACGAGGAGAAGAUCCAGACCGUGUUCGAGCAGCUGGUGCUGGUGGACCACCCGAACAUCGUGAAGUUGCACAAGUACUGGCUGGAUACCUCUGAGGCCUGCGCGAGGGUCAUCUUCAUCACAGAGUACGUGUCAUCAGGCAGCCUCAAGCAAUUCCUCAAAAAGACCAAGAAGAACCACAAGGCCAUGAACGCCCGGGCCUGGAAGCGCUGGUGCACGCAGAUCCUGUCUGCGCUCAGCUUCCUGCACGCCUGCAGCCCCCCAAUCAUCCACGGGAACCUGACCAGCGACACCAUCUUCAUUCAGCACAACGGCCUCAUCAAGAUCGGCUCCGUGUGGCACCGAAUCUUCUCCAAUGCACUUCCAGAUGAUCUCCGAAGCCCCAUCCGCGCUGAGCGAGAGGAACUUCGGAACCUGCACUUCUUCCCCCCAGAGUAUGGAGAGGUGGCCGAUGGGACCGCUGUGGACAUCUUCUCCUUUGGGAUGUGUGCGCUGGAGAUGGCUGUACUGGAAAUCCAGACCAAUGGGGACACCCGGGUCACAGAGGAGGCCAUUGCUCGCGCCAGGCACUCGCUGAGUGACCCCAACAUGCGGGAGUUCAUCCUUUGCUGCCUGGCCCGGGACCCUGCCCGCCGGCCCUCUGCCCACAGCCUCCUCUUCCACCGCGUGCUCUUCGAGGUGCACUCGCUGAAGCUCCUGGCAGCCCACUGCUUCAUCCAGCACCAGUACCUCAUGCCUGAGAAUGUGGUGGAGGAGAAGACCAAGGCCAUGGACCUGCACGCGGUCUUGGCGGAGCUUCCCCGGCCCCGCAGGCCCCCGCUGCAGUGGCGGUACUCGGAAGUCUCCUUCAUGGAGCUGGACAAAUUCCUGGAGGAUGUCAGGAAUGGAAUCUACCCACUGAUGAACUUUGCAGCCACUCGACCCCUGGGGCUGCCCCGUGUGCUGGCCCCACCCCCGGAGGAGGUCCAAAAGGCCAAGACCCCGACGCCAGAGCCCUUUGACUCUGAGACCAGAAAGGUCAUCCAGAUGCAGUGCAACCUGGAGAGAAGCGAGGACAAGGCGCGCUGGCAUGUGAGCGGGGCCUGGGAGGGCGGCGCUGCCGUGGGGAAGGCGGGAGCGUGGCGGAGCCCUGAACCCCCAGCCGACCACGCCCCGCCGCCUCCCCAGCUCACUCUGCUUCUGGUGCUGGAAGACCGGCUGCACCGGCAGCUGACCUACGACCUGCUCCCAAGUAGGCUGGGCAGGGGACUUGGGCGGCGGGCGGUGACCCCAGGCGGCGGGUGGGCAGCGGCCUCAUGCCUCGCCUUACGCCAUUGCCUCAGCGGACAGCGCCCAGGACCUCGCCUCGGAGCUCGUGCACUAUGGCUUCCUCCACGAGGUGCGCUGGGCGGUGCGGCGCGGCCUGGCGGAGGGGGCGCACGGGGCAGGCCGCGCCCCUCCGUCCCCCAUGCCUCCCUCCUUCCGCAGGACGACCGGAUGAAGCUGGCCGCCUUCCUGGAGAGCACCUUCCUCAAGUACCGUGGGACCCAGGCCUGACCCGGAGCCCCAGCCCCAGGGGACCAUGCCGGGGUGCUGCCUGGGCAGGCCAUGUUGGGGAGACUCCAGCACCGUGGGGCUGCCCUCCUCCAUGCGCCUGGGAGCACAAAGGCCCCGGUAGUGAAGGAACCCCCCGUCUCCUGAGAGUGGGGCUGACCCUGCCUUGGGCGCCGAGGGGUUGGGGGGUGGGUGUGGGGGAGCCGUUAGGCCUCCCAGGUCCUUAGGAUCAGGGUUGCCCCCAGAACCCCUUCCCAUAUCCUCCAUUCUCCGCCCUGAGUUCCUACCCAGGCUGCCUGGCCGGGGCCACUGCCUCCUCAGCAUGCAGGAGGCUGCCCUGUAGGGAACCCCAGCUCUGGGGCUUGGGGGUGAGGGUCAGCCCUGGACAGACCUCUGCCCAGGGAACUGCUCCAUGGGGUCUGGGAGAGCAGCCAUCCCCUGCUGGCACCAUAGACCCACACAAGGAGCCUGCACAGCAAGCCAGCGGUGACACACCUGCAGGUGUCAGGCAUGGCACUGGGCACAACAGGGACCUGGCAGGAGAAACAGACCACAGAGAGGUCUGGAGUUGAGGCUGUUGUCAGCAAAGCCCCUGGUCCCACACAGCUCUGCCCUAGAGCCACCUCUUUGACCCUUUACCCACCCUGAGACCAGAACUUGCAGCCCCUCUGCAGAUCUCCUCUGGCCACUGCAGCCCCUCCAAUGGGCUUUUUCUCUCAUGCAUUCCCUGGCCUGGAGGCGUCAGGGACCCCACAUCCUCCCUGCUCCUCAGACUCACAGCCCCUCCAUGUUACCUCCCGCACCUCCUCCCUGGGGCAGCUGCUCCCUGGGCCUCUGAGGAUGUCAGCUCCUGGCUCCCUGCCUCUCUCCCACUCCACUCCUGGCUCAGUCUUAGAGAUUUCUAUGCCCUCAUGGAUUCUACCCCUGCCUUCCUGGCCUCUUGAUUCUUGGCUUGCCUCUCCUCCAAUUCCAAACUUAGUGAAAUGGCCUUAAGCAUUUUAAACUGUAUGUAUACAUUAGCGCAUUCAUGCCUUUCUAAACGCAUUUCAAAUGUCAACCAGGAAGGCACACCACUGUAUUAGUUUUAUACUGCCGCUGUAAAAUUUACCACAAACUUAGUGACUUAACACAAAUUUAUUGCAAUUCUGUAGGCUGGAAGUCUGACUAUGGGUCUCACUGGACUAGAAUCAAGGCUGGCAGGCUGCCUUCCUUCCUGGAGGUUCUAGGGGAGACUCUGUCUCCUGCUCCUUCAGGCUGCUGGCAGAAUCCACAUCCUUUCGGUGGCAGGGCCAAGGUCCCCACUUUCUUGCUGACUGUAAACUAAGGCCACUUCCAGCUUGUAGAGGCUGCCUACAUUCCUUGGCUCUUGGCCCCCUCCUCCAUCUUCAGAGCUAGCAGGUUCAGUCUGUGUCACGAACCAUUUCUCUGGUUCCCUGCAGACAGGAAAGGUUGUCCCUAAGGACUCAUGAGAUUAGGUUGGGCCCAGCCAGAUAAUACAUGAUAAUCUCCCUCCUCAAGGUUUUUAAUAUUAAACACAUCUGCAGGACACAUUUUGCCAUGUAAACUAACAUUCACUGGUUCCAGGGAUUAAGGAAUGAACCUCUUUUGUUGGGGAAGGGUGGCAUUCUGCUGACCACAGCACUCCAACCAAAAGCCAAAAACCAAAGCAAGACUUACUAACGCAUAUCAAAUAAAUUAAAGGUACAAAAUCGUGAAUCUCAGUUAUCUUAAAUAUUCCAAUACUAUUUACAAAAUUAUUCAAAUUCUCACGCCUUCCAACUCAAAAUUAGCAAUCUAAAGUAAUUUCCAUAUCCUAGAUGGAAACCCUCAUGCUAAACUGUCUGAUUAUGCAUGGUUCUAAAUGGUUUCAGUGGCAAAUACAUAACAUUGUACUACUGAUUAAACUGAACUUAAAAGCA